UCGCCCUUUUAUCAACACAUUAGCACACAGUCAGCACACAUCAACACGACUCAGCACAUGCUGGGCCACUGUACACUCAGCACCUACUUGGUCAGUGCACGUCAGCAUGUGCUUAGCGUACGCUCGGUCAGCAAACACUCAGCACAUGCUUGGUCAACACACAUCAGCACGUGCUCAGCGCACAGUCAGCACACACUCGGUACACGCUCGGUCGGCGCACGUCAGCACAUGCUCAGCGCACAGCACACACUCGGCACACGGUCAUCACACGUCAGCUUGUGCCCAGCGCACAGUCAGCACACACUCAGCACACGGUCAGCGCACAUCAGCACGUGCUCAGCGCACAGUCAGCACACAGCACACACUCGGUCAGCGCACGUCAGCAUGUGCUCAGCGCACAGUCAGCACACACGGCACAUACGUGCUUAGUGCACAUCAGCACAUGCUCAGCACACACUUGGCACACUCGUUUAGCACACUACACAUGCUCAGCACACGGUCAGUGCACGUCAGCACAUGCUCAGCACACUUGGUACACUUGUUUAGCACUACUAUGCUUGGCACACACUUGGUCAGCGCACGUCAGCACGUGCUCAGCGCACAGUCAGCACACAUUCGGCACACAUUUAGCACACUACAUGCUUGGCACACACUCAGCGCACCUCAGCAUGUGUUCAGUGCACAGUCAGCACACACUCGGCACACACUCGGUCAGCGCACGUCAGCACGUGCUCAGCGCACAGUCAGCACACAUUCGGCACACAUUUAGCACACUACAUGCUUGGCACACACUCAGCGCACCUCAGCAUGUGUUCAGUGCACAGUCAGCACACACUCGGCACACACUCGGUCAGCGCACGUCAGCACGUGCUCAGUGCAUGCCUGGUCAUUUUACACUCAGCACAUACUCACCGCAUGCUUGGUCGGCACAGUCAGCACAUGCUCGGUGAAUGCGCACUUGGUCAACACGUGUGGUCAGCACACAGUCAGCACAGCCUGAAGAGCCUGGUGUGUCCCGGGCACUGAACUGUACAUUUGAAUAAAGGAGGAAUUGGUCGGAGUCCCCCGCUUUGACCUCACAUUUCAUAAUGUCAAUCCUGCCACGUGCAUUACAGCCUAGCCCUCGGCGACUUGCUGUUGGCGGACUGGCGUACAGGGAGGUGUCACUCUUAGUCACCUGCCCUAGGGCUCAGCUCAGAUGUUAGCAGAUCCCUCGGCGAGCCUUUCCAUGGCCUCCCUCCUGUUUUCCACGCACCAUUCUCUGUGUGGUUGCCUGUGUCUCCUGGCCAACUGAGCUGUGGUUUGAGGUUCAUCUUCCGUGCCAGCUUUAUCUGUGUUACUCUCUCCUUCUCCACAGUCACUUAAAUAUUAAUACAGACACACCCAGAAAGACCUGGAAAAUUCACCUAGCUCAAGCAAGCGUGGCUUUUUCCUUGGCUACUUCAUUUUGUAAUGCCUUACAACAGCGUUGUGAAAGAGGGGAUAGAUUGUUUCUUCAAAUAUGAAAAAACAGAAUUGUCUUGAAGCAGCCCAAGAUUAUAGGGGUGUCCUCCCACAGGGCUGGCCCAUGUCAGAUCAUAGGGGUGUCUUCCGACAGGGCGGGCCCACACUCAGAUCACAAGGGAGUCCUUCAACAGGGCUGGCCCGGACUCUGCAGCUCUGCUGACUCCUGUGACACCUAUGGUCUGUCAGAGCCGAGCUCUCCUGAAGCACUUGUGAGAGCCUGGGCUGGUGCUGGGGGCUCUUCCUGCCCCUGUGUCUGAGACCAUAGGACCUGUCCCCAUCGACGGAGCUGAAGCUUUACAAGUUCUGCAGAGAGAAUUUCGGUCUUUGUAACAUUUAGGCUGAGUUCUAAAACUCACUUUUGGAGUCUGAUUUCCAGCGUCCGCCAUGUUUGAAAAGGCCCCGUGUGCUUUUC